ACCCGGAUAUGGUUAUGGGCUCGGAAAUCUAGUUCGGGAAAAGUGUGAGGGGCUCUUCACGUGGGGAAGGAACAGCAGGCGCGGAGGAGGGGGCAAGCGUGUGUGAGAUUCAGUGGUCCAUGCGUGCGUUUGUCGUGUAAGGGUCAUUCCUGGGGUUUGGAGUGGGGGAACAAAUCAAUGUGGCUGUUUUUCCGUGGAAAGAAUUCCCACUGCAGUGUCCCGGAGCCUGCGUGUGGUGGGCAAGCUCCUCAAAUGGUAUCUCACAGGGAAUAGGGGAGUCUUGAAAACGCAGCUUCGGCAGUAGGAACAUGAACCUCUUACCUAAAAGUUCCAGGGAGUUUGGCUCCGUUGACUAUUGGGAGAAGUUCUUCCAGCAGCGAGGAAAGAAAGCUUUCGAGUGGUAUGGAACCUACCUGGAACUGUGCGGGGUGCUACAUAAAUAUAUCAAGCCCAGGGAAAAGGUGCUGGUGAUUGGGUGUGGCAACUCAGAACUGAGUGAGCAACUGUAUGAUGUGGGCUAUCGGGAUAUAGUGAACAUCGACAUCAGUGAGGUUGUCAUCAAGCAAAUGAAGGAAUGUAAUGCCACCCGACGGCCCCAGAUGAGCUUCUUGAAGAUGGACAUGACGCAGAUGGAGUUUCCUGAUGCCUCGUUCCAGGUGGUGUUGGACAAGGGCACCCUGGAUGCUGUCCUGACAGAUGAGGAAGAGAAGACCUUACAACAGGUGGACAGGAUGCUGGCUGAGGUUGGCCGUGUCCUGCAGGUGGGCGGUCGCUAUCUCUGCAUCUCCCUGGCUCAGGCUCACAUCCUGAAGAAAGCAGUGGGCCACUUCUCCCGGGAGGGGUGGAUGGUGAGGGUGCACCAAGUGGCCAACAGCCAGGACCAGGUGUUGGAAGCAGAGCCUCAGUUCUCCUUGCCUGUCUUUGCCUUCAUCAUGACCAAGUUCAGGCCAGUCCCUGGCUCUGCCCUUCAGAUCUUUGAGCUGUGUGCUCAGGAGCAGCGCAAGCCUGUGCGGCUGGAGAGUGCCGAGCGGCUGGCCGAGGCGGUGCAGGAGCGACAGCAGUAUGCCUGGCUGUGCAGCCAGCUGCGCCGCAAGGCCAGGCUGGGGAGUGUGUCUCUGGACUUGUGCGAUGGGGACACGGGGGAGCCACGCUACACCCUCCACGUGGUGGACAGCCCCACUGUGAAACCAUCGCGGGACAAUCAUUUUGCGAUUUUCAUCAUCCCUCAGGGCCGGGAGACCGAGUGGCUCUUUGGCAUGGAUGAGGGCCGGAAACAGCUGGCGGCCAGUGCUGGCUUCAGGAGGUUGAUUACAGUGGCCCUUCACCGAGGUCAGCAGUAUGAAAGCAUGGACCACAUCCAAGCUGAGCUGUCGGCUAGAGUCAUGGAGCUGGCCCCAGCUGGGAUGCCCACCCAGCAGCAGGUCCCCUUUCUGUCUGUGGGUGGGGACAUUGGGGUCCGGACCGUUCAGCACCAAGACUGCAGCCCCUUGAGCGGUGACUAUGUCAUUGAGGAUGUGCAAGGGGAUGACAAGCGAUACUUCCGUCGACUGAUCUUCCUCAGCAACAGGAAUGUGGUGCAGUCCGAAGCCAGGUUGCUGAAGGAUGUGUCUCACAAAGCCCAGAAGAAGCGGAAAAAGGACAGGAAGAAGCAGCGGCCUGCUGAUGCGGAGGACCUCCCUGCAGCCCCGGGGCAGUCCAUUGAUAAGAGUUACCUGUGUUGUGAACACCACAAAGCCAUGAUCGCUGGCCUUGCCCUGCUGAGAAACCCAGAGCUACUCCUAGAGAUCCCACUGGCAUUGUUGGUGGUAGGCCUGGGCGGGGGCAGCCUCCCCCUCUUUGUCCACGAUCAUUUUCCAAAGUCCUGCAUUGAUGCUGUGGAGAUCGAUCCCUCCAUGUUGGAAGUGGCCACCCAGUGGUUUGGCUUCUCCCAGAGUGACCGAAUGAAGGUCCACAUUGCAGAUGGCCUGGACUAUAUCGCCAGCUUGGCAGGAGGAGGAGAAGCACGGCCUUGCUACGAUGUCAUAAUGUUUGAUGUUGACAGUAAGGACCCAACACUGGGAAUGAGUUGUCCGCCCCCAGCAUUUGUGGAGCAAUCUUUUCUACAGAAGGUUAAAAGCAUCUUGACUCCUGAAGGUGUUUUUAUUCUCAACCUUGUGUGCCGAGACUUGGGGCUAAAAGACUCAGUGCUGGCUGGGCUCAAGGCAGUGUUCCCCCUCCUAUAUGUCCGGCGAAUUGAGGGUGAAGUGAAUGAGAUCCUGUUCUGUCAGCUGCACCCUGAGCAAAAACUUGCCACACCAGAGCUCCUAGAAACAGCCCAGGCUUUGGAGCGGACCCUGAGGAAGCCUGGGAGGGGUUGGGAUGACACGUAUGUCUUGUCAGAUAUGCUCAAGACGGUGAAAAUUGUGUGACUGCUUAGGCCAAGCAGCCCUCCUGCCUAGACUGACCUUGGACUCCCAGCCUGCCAGAGAAUGAAGAAAUACAACGCACAGUACUUUUGAAGCUUCGUAUUUUUCUUGGUUUCACACUCAGCUACAUGUGACCUCCAGCUUGGUGAGGUUGCCUGAAGAUUAGGGAAAAUAAAAAUGUCCUUCCCAUCUUGUCCUCUUCAGUACCACUUGGGUUGGUUUGUCUUUGCUUCCUACACCACGUCCUUGAGUGGAGUUCCCUGCUGAAGCCCCUAGCACACACUGCAUGCCUUAACAAGUGUGUGCAAGCCCCUCAGAACUCAAGACAUCCAAAUUUUAUUGCGUCUCUACUUAUACUGGUUUGCUUUUGAUUUAUUCCUCUAUUAGUUCUAUAGGAGUGAUCUCAAGUGAGAUAGCAGAGCAAGAUGCCAAAAGACCAUAAAUAGAGUAAGGUUUCUAUAGAUGUGAGACAGAUUUGAGAGAGCAUUUACUCUGUCUCCCUGUGGAUGAAACUGCUGCUGAAAUGGUUCCAAUUUUUAGGAAUCUGCUUACCCACUUCAUUAUUUGACAGCUUUCCUUGGUGACCCAAACCUUGUAGCCUAAGCCAUUUGUCUUUUUCUCAGUGGAGGGAGUGUAUGGACCUGGCCCCAUGGCUUUGCAUGUUAGAGACCUGGCAGACUAAAGUCUCUAGUGUUUGUUUGCUCACAUUUGCUGAGUGACAGCUAUGUGCCAGACUGCAUAAAGGGUGGUGGCAGAAGUGAAAAUGUUUAAGAAUGACCAAAAACAUUAGUAAUGAAAGUUAAUGUGUUCCAGGCAUUCUUCUAAGUGGUUUACAUGCACUGUCUCAUUUAAUCUGAGAUAAAGGAUACUUAAGCCCAAACUAUAUCUAAACCCAAAUCUCACUUGGCUGGAAACAUCAAUCUUAACCAUUUAUUCAGAACCAUUAAACCAAUGAUUCCAAGA